CUCCCUUCCUUCUUUCCUUGCUUUCGCCGCGCACUCCGCCGCCAUGGAGCAGCGCCGCGUCACCGACUUCUUCGCGCGCCGCCGCCCCGGGCCCCCCCGCAUCGCGCCGCCCAAGCUGGCCUGCCGCACCCCCAGCCCCGCCAGGCCCGCACUCCGCGCCCCGGCCUCCGCUACCAGUGGCAGCCGCAAGCGCGCCCGCCCGCCCGCCGCCCCCGGACGCGACCAGGCCAGGCCACCGGCCCGCAGGAGACUGCGGCUGUCGGUGGACGAGGUUUCCAGCCCCAGUACCCCCGAGGCCCCAGACAUCCCAGCCUGCCCUUCUCCGGGCCAGAAGAUAAAGAAAUCCACCCCGGCAGCAGGUCAGCCGCCCCACCUGACAUCCGCGCAGGACCAGGACACCAUCUCUGAGCUUGCGUCAUGCCUGCAACGGGCCCGGGAGCUGGGGGCAAGAGUCCGGGCGCUGAAGGCCAGUGCCCAGGAUGCUGGGGAGUCCUGCACCCCAGAGGCCGAGGGCCGCCCUGAGGAGCCAUGUGGCGAGAAGGCGCCCGCCUACCAGCGCUUCCAUGCCCUGGCCCAGCCCGGCCUGCCGGGACUCGUGCUGCCCUACAAGUACCAGGUGCUGGCGGAGAUGUUCCGCAGCAUGGACACCAUCGUGGGCAUGCUCCACAACCGCUCCGAGACGCCCACCUUUGCCAAGGUCCAGCGGGGCGUCCAGGACAUGAUGCGUAGGCGUUUUGAGGAGUGCAAUGUUGGCCAGAUCAAAACCGUGUACCCGGCCUCCUACCGCUUCCGCCAGGAGCGCAGUGUCCCCACCUUCAAGGAUGGCACCAGGAGGUCAGAUUACCAGCUCACCAUCGAGCCACUGCUGGAGCAGGAGGCUGACGGAGCAGCCCCCCAGCUCACGGCCUCGCGCCUCCUGCAGCGACGGCAGAUCUUCAGCCAGAAGCUGGUGGAGCAUGUCAAGGAGCACCACAAGGCCUUCCUGGCCUCCCUGAGCCCCGCCAUGGUGGUGCCGGAGGACCAGCUGACCCGCUGGCACCCGCGCUUCAACGUGGAUGAAGUACCCGACAUCGAGCCGGCCGCGCUGCCCCAGCCACCCGCCACGGAGAAGCUCACCACUGCUCAGGAGGUGCUGGCCCGGGCCCGCAACCUGAUUUCACCCAGGAUGGAGAAGGCCUUGAGUCAAUUGGCCCUGCGCUCUGCUGCGCCCAGCAGCCCCGGGUCUCCCAGGCCAGCACUGCCGGCUACCCCACCAGCCACCCCGCCUGCAGCCUCUCCCAGUGCUCUGAAGGGGGUGUCCCAGGAUCUGCUGGAGCGGAUCCGAGCCAAGGAGGCACAGAAGCAGCUGGCACAGAUGACGCGGUGCCCGGAGCAGGAGCAGCGGCUGCAGCGCUUAGAACGGCUGCCUGAGCUGGCCCGCGUGCUGCGGAGCGUCUUUGUGUCCGAACGCAAGCCUGCGCUCAGCAUGGAGGUGGCCUGUGCCAGGAUGGUGGGCAGCUGUUGUACUAUCAUGAGCCCUGGGGAAAUGGAGAAGCACCUGCUGCUCCUCUCCGAGCUGCUGCCGGACUGGCUCAGCCUCCACCGCAUCCGCACCGACACCUACGUCAAGCUGGACAAGGCCGCGGACCUCGCCCACAUCACUGCACGCCUGGCCCACCAGACACGUGCUGAGGAGGGGCUGUGAGCCUGGGGGCCACUGUGGACAGACGUGGGCUUCAGAAGCUCGCUGGCCUGGGCCCACCAGCAUUUUCUUUUAUGAACAUGAUACACUUUGGCCUUCCUUUCCCCAGCGCCCCUGAGGGCCAGAGGCAGAUGUGGGCUGCAGGCUGCACAGCCCGAGGGUCUCUGGCUGCGGGCGGUGGGCCCCUUCAUGGGGCUCACCUGGUGGAUUCACAUUAAACCGGUUUCUGUGGGCACCUCUGUCCUUGCUGCUGGUGGGGAAGGGAAGCCAGAUCCAGCACCCCCUGGGGGGCCAUCGGGAGUGUGGCUGGGGGUGAAGGGGGCUCUGUGGCAAUAUGGGGUUGGGUAGUGUGGGUGGCAGGCCAUCCCCUCUAAUCUUGGAACCUCUGAAUAUGGGACCUCCCACAGCAAAGGGUGACUUUUGUCAUUAAGAAAGACUGGGGUGGGUGUGGUGGCUCACGCCUGUAACCCCAGCACUUUGGGAGGCCAAGGUGGGCAGAUCACGAGGUCAAGAGAUCGAGACCAUCCUGGCGAACAUGGUGAAACCCCAUCUCUACUAAAAAUACAAAAAAUUAGCCGGGUGUGGUGGUGGGCACCUGUCGUCCCAGCUACUAGGGAGGCUGAGGCAGGAGAAUGGUGUGAACCCAGGAGGCACAGCUUGCAGUGAGCGAAGAUCGCACCACUGCACGCACUCCAGCCUGGGUGACAGAGCGAGACUCCGUCUCAAAAAAAAAAAUUUCAAGACUGGAGAGGUGAUCCUGAAUUGUCCAGCUACGCCCCAUGUCAUCACAGGGCCUUCAUGACAGGGCCAGAGCCAGCCAGCUUUGAAGACGCGGCCCUGCCCCGACACAGGCAGCCUGGAGAAGCUGGGCAGGACAAGUAGGACAUCCCUGGAGCCUCCAGAAGGGACUGGCCUCUGCCCACACCUUGACUUCAGUAUUUCUGACCUCCUAAACUCUAAUAAAGUCAUGCUUACAGCCACUA